AACGCUUUUUAAACGCUUGGCCUCUGUGUUACAGCCAGUUAAAAAAAACAAGGAGUAGAGAUACGAAUGGGGUGUAGUAGCCGACUGCUCGCAGGCACCCCCAGGUUAUGUGGACAGAGCUAAGCCCAAAGUUGUGAUUUUCCACUCUGUUCUGUCCAUGUCGAGGGAAGAUAAGUAGAAAGUGACACAGUAAGAGCCAGAAUACACCAGGUGAAGGAGAGAAUUGCAUUGUGUUUUGAGAAGUUUCACUGACAAGUUAUCCUGGGCUGUGGGACAUCACUAGCUUUGAAAGUGUAGCUGGCACCUCGUCCAUCUAAUUUGAUGGGUGUGUGUGGGGUGUUGGGCACGCGUCGGCCUAGCAGAUCUGAACCCAGGUGAUUUCUGUUCUCAGGAAGCUUUUAGGUGACAAGGAUCAGGCAUGUGAACAAAUAACCAUACUGUAAAGCUGGCUGUGCUGGGUCGCUAGAGCAAACUCAGACACACACUCUGCGCUCUUGGAGUUGGGAAACCCACCUGCGUUGGCUUUUUGUGGGAGGUGGCCUUGAUUGGGCCUUGAAGGAUGGGUGAGAUUUACAGAAGGUUGGAAUGAGGCACUCCAAGCAAAGAACAGCAGAGGCUCAGCAGCAAGAAUGCAAAAAGGGAGUUCACUACUGACUCAAAUACCCGGAGCCCUGGGGUUUAGUCUCCUCCCUCCACAAGUCACAUGUAAAAGUCCAGUCAUGCUGGGCGCGGUGGCUCAUGCCUAUAAUCCUAGCACUUUGGGAGGCCGAGGUGGGCGGAUCAUGAGGUCAGUAGUUCAAGAACAACCUGGCCAACACGGUGAAACCCUGUCUCUACUAAAAAUACAAAAAUUAGUCGGGCAUGGUGGCGGGCACCUGCAAUCCCAGCUACUCGAGAGGCUGAGGCAGGAGAAUCACUUGAAACUGGAAGGCGGAGGUUGCAGUGAGCCGAGAUCAUGCCACUGCAUUCCAGCCUGGGCGAAAGAGCUAAACUCCGUCUCUCAAAAAAAAAAAAAAAAAAAAAAGUCCAGUCAUGUAAUUAUGUAACAGUCACGUGACCUGUUAUGGAACUUCCAAUGGCAACUAAAAGCACAUGCAGCUAGUGGAUUUCAUCGGAGUGUUUGAGGUUCCCGUCUUGAAUGUGACUGUCGGAACUACUGUCCGGGGGGGUGGUGCAUUUUUCUGAGUUUAAGCAGGAGUCGGGAGUCCCCAAAAGGGAACACAAGACACCUUGAUCCUGGCAUAUCUUGUGUGCCCUCUGUGGGCCUCAGUUUGUUUCACAGGAUUGAAAACCUGGGAAGUUAGAUGCUCAUCUCAUCUGAAGAAGUUGUUCUGCCUUUGUUAAGGUGGAGCGGGAAUAGUCAGCACUGGGACAUGAGAAUGGACAGUCGCCUGGACCCACCUAGGGAUUCACCAUUUGCUAAAUGUGCAGCGUCUAUCCCAGACUACCGGGGCCCUAAUGGAGUGUGGACACUGCUUCAGAAAGGGAGAAGCGUUAGUGCUGCCGACCUGAGCGAGGCCGAGCCAACCCUCACCCACAUGAGCAUCACCCGUCUGCAUGAGCAGAAGCUGGUGCAGCAUGUGGUGUCUCAGAACUGUGACGGGCUCCACCUGAGGAGUGGGCUGCCGCGCACGGCCAUCUCCGAGCUCCACGGGAACAUGUACAUUGAAGUCUGUACCUCCUGCGUUCCCAACAGGGAGUACGUGCGGGUGUUCGAUGUGACGGAGCGCACUGCCCUCCACAGACACCAGACAGGCCGGACCUGCCACAAGUGUGGGACCCAGCUGCGGGACACCAUUGUGCACUUUGGGGAGAGGGGGACGUUGGGGCAGCCUUUGAACUGGGAAGCGGCGACCGAGGCUGCCAGCAGAGCAGACACCAUCCUGUGUCUAGGGUCCAGCCUGAAGGUUCUAAAGAAGUACCCACGCCUCUGGUGCAUGACCAAGCCCCCUAGCCGGCGGCCGAAGCUUUACAUCGUGAACCUGCAGUGGACCCCGAAGGAUGACUGGGCUGCCCUGAAGCUACAUGGGAAGUGUGAUGACGUCAUGCGGCUCCUCAUGGCCGAGCUGGGCUUGGAGAUCCCCGCCUAUAGCAGGUGGCAGGAUCCCAUUUUCUCACUGGCGACUCCCCUGCGUGCUGGUGAAGAAGGCAGCCACAGUCGGAAGUCGCUGUGCAGAAGCAGAGAGGAGGCCCCGCCUGGGGACCGGGGUGCACCGCUUAGCUCGGCCCCCAUCCUAGGGGGCUGGUUUGGCAGGGGCUGCACAAAACGCACAAAAAGGAAGAAAGUGACGUAAUCACGUGCUCGAUGAAGAACAGUUGGCACUUUGCAGAUGGCCAGUGUCACGGUGAAGGCUGGGUUGCCCCCACGGGUCUAGGGAGAACGAACUCUUUGGGGAUGACAUUUUCACCGUGACAUUUUUAGCCAUUUGUCCUUGAGGAAGCCCCUUGCACUGCUGCGGUUGUACCCUGAUACGGCCUGGCCAUCGAGGACACCUGCCCAUCCGGCCUCUGUGUCAAGAGGUGGCAGCCGCACCUUUCUGUGAGAACGGAACUCGGGUUAUUUCAGCCCCGGCCUGCAGAGUGGAAGCGCCCAGCGGCCUUUCCUCGCUCACCAGGCCAGUCUCAGGGCCUCACCGUAUUUCUACUACUACUUAAUGAAAAAGUGUGAACUUUAUAGAAUCCUCUCUGUACUGGAUGUGCGGCAGAGGGGUGGCUCCGAGCCUCGGCUCUAUGCAGACCUUUUUAUUUCUAUUAAACGUUUCUGCACUGGC